AUGCUUCUACUCAGAGCCCCCAAAGCAGGGGAGCCUCCACUCCUCUGUCUGCAGCCUCCCCUGUCGGUUCUCGCUACCCAGGGUUCAGUGGCCUGGGGGCUGACGGAGCUCUUACCCUUUCACAGCUGGGGAGUGGACCUGGGCCUGCGCCUCUCCGCGCCAGCGCCUGCGCUGUGCGCCUCUCCGCGCCUGCGCCGCCGCUGUGCGCCUCUCCGCCGCUGUGCGCCUCUCCGCCGCUGUCCGCCUCUCCACCGCGCCGCCGCUGUCGGCCUCUCCGCCGCGCCGCCGCUGACCGACUCUCCGCUGCGCCGCCGCUAUCCGCCUCUCCGCCGCUGUCCGCCUCUCCGCCGCGCCGCCGCUGUCCGCCUCUCCGCCGCGCCGCCGCUGUCCGCCUCUCCACCGCGCCGCCGCUGUCGGCCUCUCCGCCGCGCCGCCGCUGACCGACUCUCCGCUGCGCCGCCGCUAUCCGCCUCUCCGCCGCUGUCCGCCUCUCCGCCGCGCCGCCGCUGGCCGCCUCUCCGCCGCGCCAACGCUGGCCGCCUCUCCGCCGCUGGCCGCCUCUCCGCCGCGCCGCCGCUGGCCGCCUCUCCGCCGCGCCGCCGCUGGCCGCCUCUCCGCCGCGCCAACGCUGGCCGCCUCUCCGCCGCUGUCCGCCUCUCCGCCACGCCGGCACCAGCGCUGUGUGCUUUUGCAAGGGCGGAGCUGCGUUCUCCUCGGCACAGACCCGGAGAGCAUUGCGAGGGCGGAGCUGCGUUCUGCUCUGCACAGACCUUGGGGCACUGCCUCGCUUUGGGACAACUCGGGGCCGCAUCGACGGUGAAUAAAAUCCUUCCUGUUUGCAGCCAUGUUUGUGGUUGGUGGCAGCGAUGGACACUGCAGCCAGCCAGAGUGUAGAAAAAGGCAUCGGGUGAAAGAAGAUGGCCACGGAGACAGACAGCAGCGUGGUCAGAGUGGUAGGAGCCGGCCAUCAGCGAGAGCUGCUCCAUGCCUGGCUGCUGGGAGCUAGAGCCUGCGGCCCACUGGCUUGCCUCACUGUAGUUGGUGGUGGCGGUGACAGAGACUGCAGCAUGACCAGAGUGGCUUUUCUGGCUUUGCCCACCCAGCUGCUCCGUGCCAGGAGGAGGAGGAGACACCUAGAGCGUGCAACACCACGGCUCGCCUCGCUGCGGGUGGGUGGCAGUGACGGAGACUGCAGUGCACCAGAACGGAUGGAGCUUGACUUGCCCAAAUUGCUAUGUACAUAUUAAAGAGAGGCUGGAACUGAAGUUGGUCAUUUCUCACUGGAUCAGUCAACAAGAUUUGAGUACUUUCUGUGUGCUCUGCAUCAUUCUGAGUACUCUGGGGGACAGAAUAAGGCAUGGCUCCUGCCUUCAAGGAGUAUGGAAUUUAAUAGAAGAUGACAACAUACAUGAUUGUAAAUCUAUCUACAUGAGAGUGCCUAAUUGUGAGAUUCCUAAUAAACGGCAAGAUAUGUUCUGAAAAUCUGAAACAUAAAUGAGGUUGAAGAAAUUGUGAAAAGUUUAGCAGAGGAGGAAUAAUUCGUCAGGUUCUUUAAACACAAGUAAAGGGGAAAGGAAGGACCAUUUUUAAGUUUAGAUAUUCCAAGCGUUAGUGGUGAGGUUGAUUAUGGUAUGUCUUCUCGUUGAUGAGGGAGGAGACUGGUGAAUAGUGGAAAAUAAAGUUAAAUAGCUAGGGUGGGGCCAAAUUCUGGGUUUUAAUAAAAGCCAGGCAUAGAAAUUUAGAUUGGGGUGGUAGAAAAAGGAAGGCUUUAAUAGUUUUUGAUCCAAUGAAUGACAUCAUACAAGUUCUAUAUAAAGAGCAGUGAUUUCAGGAUGGGAGAGAAUGGCAUCAGGAAGACCCACUUGAAUGCUGGUAAGUAAUGUUACUAACAGUGCCAUUAGUAACAUUAAUGUUACUAGGGCCUGGACUGAUAUGCUGAUGGAAGUGAGAAUGAAGAAUAAGGUGGGAUGAAAGAGAUUUUGACAAGAGUUUUUUAAUGAACCUGAAACGGGAAAGGGCGAGAUUAACUAAGCCUGUUUGCCAUGGACAGCAAUGGGGUUGCUAGAAGAUUAGCUGUGCGGAAAAAUUAUGCAUUUACCUUUGGGCAUAAUAAAAUGCAAUUGACUCUCCAUAUUCAUGGGUUCUGCAUCCACUGAUUCAAACAACUGUGGAACAAAAUUGUCAGAAAAAACAAUACAGUGAUAAAAAAUGAUACAAAUAAAAAACAACAUGGUAUACCAACUA